GGGGGUCAAACGUGGGAUCCGACCCUUCUCCUGAGACCUUGUGUAGAGGUAGGGAAAGGUUGUCAUGGACAGGCUGCUGAGCAGAGGGAGGUUCCAGCUGGAAUGAGGGGGAGAAUCAAGAGAGGGACUGGGGCCCGUAGUGCUGAGAAAACGGGGAGCAGACCCUGCUCCUGGGUGGGUGGGCACAGGGGUGCAGAACACUGACCAGGGGCCUAAAGAGCAGGAAAUUGCUCUCACAGCUCUAGAGGCCAGAAGCCGGAAGGCGAGGAGUGGGCAGGGCCGCACUUCCUCCGGAGCUCGAGGGGAGGAUCCUGCCUGCCUUUUCCAGCUUCUGGGGCCCCAGGCGUCCUGGGAAUUCCUUGGCUUAUAGAUCCAAUCUCUGCCUCUGUCGUCACACGGCCGCCCUCUCCCUGUGUGUCUUCUUAUAAGGACACUAGUUAUGUUGGAUAACAGCCAAUCCUAGCCCGGUAUGACCUCACCUUAACUGGGUGAUAUCUGCAAAGAUCCUAUUUCCAAAUAAGGUCACAUUCACAGGGACUGUAGAUUAGGACUUAGACAUACGUUUUUAGGGACAUAAUUCAAUCUGGUGCAGAAGGGGACAGGCCUGGGUGGAGGCAGUUGACGUGCAGGAGUGGUGGGGAUGGAGGACAGAGGUGGACCUCAGCAGGCUCUGCAUAACCAGCCGUGUGUGAUGAGUGGCCACACCUUGCCUCCUCUUCCCGUCCCAGGCACCAACAGCACAGAGCAGGCCAGUGUACCCAGAGCCAUGGCAGCCACGCUGGGAGCCGGCACGCCCCCCAGGCCCCAGGCCAGGAGCAUAGCUGGGGUGUAUGUGGAGGCCUCGGGCCAGGCCCAGAGUGUCUACGCCGCCAUGGAGCAGGGCCUCCUGCCUGCUGGGCUCGGGCAGGCUCUGCUAGAGGCCCAGGCAGCCACUGGGGGCCUGGUGGACCUCGCCCGGGGCCAGCUGCUCCCUGUGUCCAAGGCCCUGCAGCAGGGUCUGGUGGGGCUGGAGCUGAAGGAGAAGCUGCUGGCCGCUGAGCGUGCCACUACGGGCUAUCCUGACCCCUACGGCGGUGAGAAGCUGGCCCUCUUUCAGGCCAUCGGGAAGGAGGUUGUGGACAGGGCCCUGGGGCAGAGCUGGCUGGAGGUCCAACUGGCCACUGGGGGCCUGGUGGACCCCGCCCAGGGAGUGCUCGUGGCCCCUGAGCCAGCCUGCCACCAGGGCCUCCUGGACCGGGAGACAUGGCACAAGCUGUCAGAGCUUGAGCCUGGCACAGGUGACCUGCGCUUCCUCGACCCCAACACGCUGGAGCGGCUGACAUACCACCAGCUGCUGGAAAGGUGUGUGCGUGCCCCCGGCUCGGGGCUAGCCUUGCUGCCCCUCAAGAUCACCUUCCGCUCCAUGGGCGGGGCGGUGAGUGCAGCUGAGCUGCUGGAGGUGGGCAUCCUGGACGAGCAGGCUGUGCAGGGUCUGCGGGAGGGCAGGCUGGCCGCAGUGGACGUGAGUGCACGUGCCGAGGUGCGGCGCUACCUGGAGGGUACCGGCAGCGUGGCCGGGGUUGUCCUGCUGCCCGAAGGCCACAAGAAGAGCUUUUUCCAGGCUGCCACCGAGCACCUGCUCCCAAUGGGCACCGCGCUGCCACUCCUAGAGGCCCAGGCUGCCACCCACACCCUGGUGGACCCCAUCACAGGCCAGCGGCUGUGGGUAGACGAGGCAGUCAGGGCGGGCCUGGUCAGCCCAGAGCUCCAUGAGCAGCUCCUGGUGGCCGAGCAGGCCGUGACAGGGCACCACGACCCCUUCAGUGGCUCCCAAAUCCCCCUUUUCCAGGCCAUGAAGAAGGGGCUAGUGGACAGGCCACUGGCACUGCGGCUCUUGGAUGCCCAGCUGGCCACAGGCGGGCUGGUCUGUCCAGCACGCAGGCUCCGGCUGCCCCUGGAGGCCGCCCUGCGCUGCGGCUGCCUGGAUGAAGACACUCAGCGGCAGCUCUCGCAGGCUGGCAGCUUCUCAGACGGCACGCACGGCGGCCUGCGCUAUGAACAGCUGCUGGCCCUCUGUGUCACCGACCCAGAGACCGGGCUUGCCUUCCUGCCACUCUCAGGGGGACCCCGGGGAGGGGAGCCCCAGGGACCCCCAUUCAUCAAGUACAGCACUCGGCAGGCCCUGAGCACGGCCACAGCCACCGUCUCUGUGGGGAAGUUCCGGGGCCGGCCCGUGUCCCUCUGGGAGCUGCUCUUCUCUGAGGCCAUCUCCUCAGAGCAGAGGGCGAUGCUGGCCCAGCAGUACCAGGAAGGGACCCUCUCCGUGGAGAAGCUGGCCGCUAAGCUGAGCGCCACCCUCGAGCAGGCUGCAGCCACUGCCAGGGUCACCUUUUCUGGGCUGAGGGACACCGUGACACCAGGAGAGCUGCUGAAAGCCGAGAUCAUCGACCAGGACCUGUACGAGCGGCUGGAGCAUGGACAGGCCACAGCCAAGGAUGUGGGCAGCCUGGCCUCGGUGCAGAGGUACCUGCAGGGUACGGGCUGCAUUGCUGGCCUGCUGCUCCCUGGCUCCCAGGAACGCCUGAGCAUCUAUGAGGCCCGAUGCAAGGGGCUCCUCCGGCCCGGCACUGCCCUCAUCCUUCUGGAGGCACAAGCUGCCACAGGCUUCAUCAUCGACCCAAAAGCAAACAAGGGGCACUCCGUUGAGGAGGCACUGAGGGCUGCUGUCAUUGGGCCUGAUGUGUUCGCGAAGCUGCUGUCGGCUGAGCGCGCUGUCACUGGCUACACUGACCCCUACACCGGGCAGCAGAUCUCCCUCUUCCAGGCCAUGCAGAAGGGCCUCAUCGUCCGGGAGCACGGCAUCCGCCUGCUGGAGGCCCAGAUCGCCACGGGCGGCGUCAUCGACCCCGUGCACAGCCACCGCGUGCCCGUGGACGUGGCCUACCGGCGCGGCUACUUCGAUCAGAUGCUGAACUUGAUCCUGUUGGACCCUUCUGACGACACCAAGGGCUUCUUCGACCCCAACACGCACGAGAACCUCACGUACCUGCAGCUUCUGGAGCGCUGUGUGCGUGACCCCGAGACGGGCCUGUACCUCCUGCCACUCAGCAGCACGCAGUCCCCGCUGGUGGACAGUGCCACCCAGCAGGCCUUCCAGAACCUGCUGCUCUCCGUGAAGUAUGGACGGUUUCAGGGGCAGAGGGUCUCCGCGUGGGAGCUGAUCAACUCUGAGUACUUCAGCGAGGGCCGCAGGAGGCAGCUGCUGCGUCGCUACCGGCAGCGCGAGGUCACGCUGGGGCAGGUGGCAAAGCUGCUGGAGGCGGAGACGCAGAGACAGGCGGACAUCAUGCUGCCCGCACUGCGGAGCCGGGUCACCGUCCACCAGCUCCUGGAGGCCGGUAUCAUUGACCAGCAGCUGUUGGACCAAGUGCUGGCCGGGACAAUCAGCCCGGAGGCCCUCCUACUCAUGGACGGCGUCCGCAGGUACCUGUGCGGCCUGGGAGCUGUGGGCGGUGUGCGGCUGCUGCCCUCUGGCCAGCGGCUCAGCCUCUACCAGGCCAUGAGGCAGAAGCUGCUGGGGCCCAGGGUGGCCCUGGCCCUGCUGGAGGCCCAGGCGGCCACCGGAACCAUCAUGGACCCUCACAGCCCAGAGAGCCUCUCGGUGGAUGAGGCCGUGCGCAGGGGUGUGGUGGGGCCGGAGCUGUAUGGCAGGCUGAAGCGGGCUGAGGGUGCCAUUGCUGGCUUCAGAGACCCCUUCUCUGGGAAGCAGGUGUCUGUGUUCCAGGCCAUGAAGAAAGGUCUCAUCCCUUGGGAGCAAGCUGCCCGCCUCCUGGAGGCUCAAGUGGCCACAGGAGGGAUCAUUGACCCCACCAGCCACCACCACCUCCCCAUGCCAGUGGCCAUUCAGCGUGGCUAUGUUGACCAGGAGAUGGAGACAGCCUUGUCCAGCUCCUCCGAAACCUUCCCCACACCGGACGGCCAGGGGCGCACGAGCUAUGCCCAGCUCCUGGAGGAGUGCCCCAGGGAUGAGACUUCUGGCCUUCACCUCCUGCCCCUGCCAGAAAGUGCUCCUGCCCUCCCCACCGAGGAGCAGGUCCAGAGGAGCCUGCAGGCCGUGCCGGGGGCCAAGGAUGGCACAUCCCUCUGGGACCUGCUCAGCUCCUGCCACUUCACCGAGGAGCAACGGAGGGGCCUGCUGGAGGACGUGCAGGAGGGGAGGACCACUGUGCCACAGCUGCUAGCCUCUGUGCAGAGGUGGGUACAGGAGACCAAGCUCCUGGCCCAGGCCCGCGUCAUGGUGCCCGGCCCACGGGGUGAGGUACCCGCUGUCUGGCUGCUGGAUGCUGGCAUCAUCACCCAGGAGACCCUUGAGGCCCUGGCUCAGGGCACGCAGUCGCCCGCCCAGGUCGCCGAGCAGCCGGCGGUGAAGGCCUGCCUGUGGGGCACAGGCUGCGUGGCCGGUGUGCUGCUACAGCCCUCUGGGGCCAAGGCCAGCAUCGCCCAGGCCGUGAGGGAUGGCCUCCUGCCCACAGGCCUGGGCCAGAGGCUGCUGGAAGCCCAGGUGGCAUCUGGCUUCCUUGUUGACCCCCUGAACAACCAGAGACUGUCAGUGGAGGACGCGGUUAAGGUCGGCCUGGUGGGCAGGGAGCUGAGUGAGCAGCUCGGGCAGGCCGAGAGGGCGGCGGCCGGGUACCCAGAUCCCUACUCUAGGGCCUCCCUCUCUCUGUGGCAGGCCAUGGAGAAGGGGCUCGUGCCACAGAACGAGGGCUUGCCCCUCCUGCAGGUGCAGCUGGCCACAGGGGGUGUGGUGGACCCUGUCCACGGGGUGCACCUGCCCCAGGCGGCAGCCUGCAGACUCGGCCUUCUGGACACACAGACGAGCCAGGUGCUGACUGCAGUUGACAAGGACAACAAGUUCUUCUUUGACCCCAGUGCGCGGGACCAGGUGACCUACCAGCAGCUCAGGGAGCGCUGCGUGUGCGACUCCGAGACCGGAUUGUUGCUGUUGCCACUGCCCUCAGACACAGUGCUUGAGGUGGACGACCACACCGCGGUGGCUCUGAGGGCCAUGAAGGUGCCCGUCAGCACAGGGAGGUUUAAGGGGUGUAGCGUGUCACUCUGGGACCUGCUGCUCUCCGAAUACGUUGGCGCUGACAAGCGGCGGGAGCUGGUGGCACUCUGUCGGUCUGGGAGGGCUGCGGCCCUGCGGCAGGUGGUCAGCGCAGUCACCACCCUGGUCGAGGCUGCAGAGAGGCAGCCCCUGCAGGCCACCUUCAGAGGGCUCCGGAAGCAGGUGUCAGCCAGGGACCUGUUCAGGGCGCAGCUGAUCAGCAGGAAGACGCUGGACGAGCUGAGCCAGGGGACAACGACUGUGAAGGAGGUGGCGGAGAUGGACAGCGUGAAGCGGUCCCUGGAGGGAGGCAACUUCAUUGCCGGGGUCCUUAUCCAGGGCACCCAGGAGAGGAUGAGCAUCCCAGAGGCCCUGAGGAGGCACAUCCUGCGGCCUGGCACAGCCCUGGUGCUGCUGGAGGCACAGGCAGCUACCGGCUUCAUCAUCGACCCCGUGGAGAACCGGAAGCUGACCGUGGAGGAGGCGUUCAAAGCAGGAAUGUUCGGGAAAGAAACCUACGUGAAGCUGCUGUCGGCCGAGCGCGCCGUCACCGGCUACACCGACCCCUAUACCGGGCAGCAGAUCUCCCUCUUCCAGGCCAUGCAGAAGGACCUCAUCGUCCGGGAGCACGGCAUCCGCCUGCUGGAGGCCCAGAUCGCCACGGGCGGCAUCAUCGACCCCGUGCACAGCCACCGCGUGCCCGUGGACGUGGCCUACCGCUGCGGCUACUUCGACGAGGAGAUGAACCGCAUCCUGGCGGACCCCAGCGACGACACCAAGGGCUUCUUCGACCCCAACACGCACGAGAACCUCACGUACCUGCAGCUUCUGGAGCGCUGUGUGGAGGACCCCGAGACGGGCCUGUACCUGCUACAAAUCAUAAAGAAAGGAGAAAACUACGUGUACAUCAAUGAGGCCACGAGACACGUGUUGCAAUCCAGAACUGCAAAAAUGCGCGUGGGGAGGUUUGCUGACCAGGUGGUCUCUUUCUGGGACCUGCUGUCCUCUCCAUACUUCACAGAGGACAGGAAGCGGGAGCUCAUCCAGGAGUAUGGAGCCCAGAGUGGGGGCCUGGAGAAAUUGCUGGAAAUCAUCACCACGACAAUUGAAGAAACAGAGACGCAAAACCAAGGCAUCAAAGUGGCGGCCAUCAGAGGGGAGGUGACAGCUGCAGACCUGUUCAACUCCAGGGUCAUCGAUCAGAAGACCCUGCACACACUUCGUGUGGGGAGGACUGGGGGACAGGCACUCAGCACGCUGGAGUGUGUGAAGCCCUAUCUGGAAGGCAGCGGCUGCAUUGCGGGGGUCACGGUGCCCUCCACCAGGGAGGUCAUGAGCCUCCAUGAGGCCAGCAGGAAGGAGCUCAUCCCUGCAGCAUUUGCGACUUGGCUGCUGGAGGCGCAGGCCGCCACCGGGUUCCUCCUGGACCCCUGCACCCGCCAGAAGCUCUCUGUGGAUGAGGCUGUGGAUGUGGGCCUGGUGAACGAGGAGCUGCGGGAGAGGCUCCUGAAGGCUGAAAGAGCUGCCACGGGCUACAGGGAUCCGGCCACAGGAGACACGAUCCCGCUGUUCCAGGCCAUGCAGAAGCAGCUCAUCGAGAAGGCGGAGGCACUGAGGCUGCUGGAGGUGCAGGUGGCCACGGGGGGUGUCAUCGACCCACAGCACCACCACCGGCUCCCACUGGAAACAGCCUACAGACGGGGCUGUCUGCACAAGGACAUCUAUGCGCUCAUUUCCGACCAGAAGCACAUGAGGAAACGGUUUGUGGACCCGAACACGCAAGAGAAGGUCUCGUACCGAGAGCUGCAGGAGAGGUGCCGCCCACAAGAGGACACGGGCUGGCUGCUGUUCCCAGUGAACAAGGCUGCACGGGACUCCGAGCACAUCGAUGACGAGACGAGAAGGGCCCUGGAGGCAGAGCAAGUGGAAAUCACAGUGGGAAGGUUCAGAGGCCAGAAACCAACACUGUGGGCACUACUGAAUUCCGAAUACGUGACAGAGGAGAAGAAGCUCCAGCUGGUGAGGAUGUAUAGAACACACACCAGACGGGCACUGCAGACGGUAGCGCAGCUCAUCUUAGAGUUGAUCGAGAAGCAGGAAACCAGCAACAAACACCUGUGGUUCCAAGGAAUUAGACGACAGAUCACAGCUUCUGAACUCCUCAGCUCAGCCAUAAUCACGGAGGAAAUGCUCCAGGACCUGGAAACGGGACGGAGCACGACGCAAGAGCUCAUGGAGGACGACCGCGUCAAGCGCUACCUGGAGGGCACCAGCUGCAUCGCGGGCGUCCUGGUGCCCGCCAAGGACCAGCCCGGCCGCCAGGAGAAGAUGAGCAUCUACCAGGCCAUGUGGAAGGGCGUGCUGCGGCCCGGCACGGCCCUGGUGCUGCUGGAGGCGCAGGCGGCCACCGGCUUCGUCAUCGACCCCGUGCGCAACCUGAGGCUGUCGGUGGAGGAGGCCGUGGCCGCGGGCGUGGUGGGCGGCGAGAUCCAGGAGAAGCUGCUGUCGGCCGAGCGCGCCGUCACCGGCUACACCGACCCCUACACCGGGCAGCAGAUCUCCCUCUUCCAGGCCAUGCAGAAGGACCUCAUCGUCCGGGAGCACGGCAUCCGCCUGCUGGAGGCCCAGAUCGCCACGGGCGGCGUCAUCGACCCCGUGCACAGCCACCGCGUGCCCGUGGACGUGGCCUACCGGCGCGGCUACUUCGACGAGGAGAUGAACCGUGUCCUGGCCGACCCCAGCGACGACACCAAGGGCUUCUUCGACCCCAACACGCACGAGAACCUCACGUACGUGCAGCUGCUGCGCCGCUGCGUGCCCGACCCGGACACCGGGCUCUACAUGCUGCAGCUGGCAGGCCGGGGCUCCGCCGUGCACCAGCUGAGCGAGGAGCUGCGCUGUGCCCUGCGCGACGCCCGCGUGACGCCAGGCUCGGGCGCCCUCCAGGGCCAGAGCGUCUCCGUCUGGGAGCUCCUCUUCUACCGCGAGGUGUCCGAGGACCGGCGCCAGGACCUGCUGAGCAGAUACCGGGCGGGCACGCUGACCGUGGAGGAGCUGGGCGCCACCCUCACCUCGCUGCUGGCCCAGGCCCAGGCCCAGGCCCGGGCCGAGGCCGAGGCCGGGAGCCCGCGCCCAGACCCCCGGGAGGCCCUGCGUGCGGCCACCAUGGAGGUCAAGGUGGGCCGCCUCCGGGGGCGCGCGGUGCCCGUGUGGGACGUGCUGGCGUCCGGCUACGUGAGCAGGGCCGCCCGGGAGGAGCUGCUGGCCGAGUUUGGCUCGGGGACCCUGGACUUGCCCGCGCUGACCCGCCGGCUGACCGCCAUCAUCGAGGAGGCCGAGGAGGCCCCCGGGGCCCGGCCGCAGCUCCAGGACGCCUGGCGCGGCCCGCGGGAGCCAGGGCCAGCCGGGCGAGGGGACGGCGACUCGGGGCGCUCCCAGCGAGAGGGCCAGGGGGAGGGCGAGACCCAGGAGGCCGCCGCCGCCGCCGCCGCCGCCGCCGCCCGCCGCCAGGAGCAGACCCUGCGUGAUGCCACCAUGGAGGUGCAGCGCGGGCAGUUCCAGGGGCGGCCGGUCUCCGUGUGGGACGUCCUCUUCUCCUCGUACCUGAGCGAGGCCCGCCGAGACGAGCUCCUGGCCCAGCACGCGGCCGGCGCCCUGGGCCUGCCCGACCUCGUCGCCGUCCUCACCCGGGUCAUCGAGGAGACCGAGGAGCGGCUCAGCAAGGUGUCCUUCCGCGGCCUGAGGCGCCAGGUGUCCGCCUCCGAGCUGCACACGUCCGGGAUCCUGGGCCCCGAGACCCUGCGGGACCUGGCCCAGGGCACUAAGACGCUGCAGGAGGUGACGGAGAUGGACUCGGUCAAGCGCUACCUGGAGGGCACCAGCUGCAUCGCGGGCGUCCUGGUGCCCGCCAAGGACCAGCCCGGCCGCCAGGAGAAGAUGAGCAUCUACCAGGCCAUGUGGAAGGGCGUGCUGCGGCCCGGCACGGCCCUGGUGCUGCUGGAGGCGCAGGCGGCCACCGGCUUCGUCAUCGACCCCGUGCGCAACCUGAGGCUGUCGGUGGAGGAGGCCGUGGCCGCGGGCGUGGUGGGCGGCGAGAUCCAGGAGAAGCUGCUGUCGGCCGAGCGCGCCGUCACCGGCUACACCGACCCCUACACCGGGCAGCAGAUCUCCCUCUUCCAGGCCAUGCAGAAGGACCUCAUCGUCCGGGAGCACGGCAUCCGCCUGCUGGAGGCCCAGAUCGCCACGGGCGGCGUCAUCGACCCCGUGCACAGCCACCGCGUGCCCGUGGACGUGGCCUACCAGCGCGGCUACUUCGACGAGGAGAUGAACCGUGUCCUGGCCGACCCCAGCGACGACACCAAGGGCUUCUUCGACCCCAACACGCACGAGAACCUCACGUACGUGCAGCUGCUGCGCCGCUGCGUGCCCGACCCGGACACCGGGCUCUACAUGCUGCAGCUGGCAGGCCGGGGCUCCGCCGUGCACCAGCUGAGCGAGGAGCUGCGCUGUGCCCUGCGCGACGCCCGCGUGACGCCAGGCUCGGGCGCCCUCCAGGGCCAGAGCGUCUCCGUCUGGGAGCUCCUCUUCUACCGCGAGGUGUCCGAGGACCGGCGCCAGGACCUGCUGAGCAGAUACCGGGCGGGCACGCUGACCGUGGAAGAGCUGGGCGCCACCCUCACCUCGCUGCUGGCCCAGGCCCAGGCCCAGGCCCGGGCCGAGGCCGAGGCCGGGAGCCCGCGCCCAGACCCCCGGGAGGCCCUGCGUGCGGCCACCAUGGAGGUCAAGGUGGGCCGCCUCCGGGGGCGCGCGGUGCCCGUGUGGGACGUGCUGGCGUCCGGCUACGUGAGCAGGGCCGCCCGGGAGGAGCUGCUGGCCGAGUUUGGCUCGGGGACCCUGGACUUGCCCGCGCUGACCCGCCGGCUGACCGCCAUCAUCGAGGAGGCCGAGGAGGCCCCCGGGGCCCGGCCGCAGCUCCAGGACGCCUGGCGCGGCCCGCGGGAGCCAGGGCCAGCCGGGCGAGGGGACGGCGACUCGGGGCGCUCCCAGCGAGAGGGCCAGGGGGAGGGCGAGACCCAGGAGGCCGCCGCCGCCGCCCGCCGCCAGGAGCAGACCCUGCGUGAUGCCACCAUGGAGGUGCAGCGCGGGCAGUUCCAGGGGCGGCCGGUCUCCGUGUGGGACGUCCUCUUCUCCUCGUACCUGAGCGAGGCCCGCCGAGACGAGCUCCUGGCCCAGCACGCGGCCGGCGCCCUGGGCCUGCCCGACCUCGUCGCCGUCCUCACCCGGGUCAUCGAGGAGACGGAGGAGCGGCUCAGCAAGGUGUCCUUCCGCGGCCUGAGGUGCCAGGUGUCCGCCUCCGAGCUGCACACGUCCGGGAUCCUGGGCCCCGAGACCCUGCGGGACCUGGCCCAGGGCACUAAGACGCUGCAGGAGGUGACGGAGAUGGACUCGGUCAAGCGCUACCUGGAGGGCACCAGCUGCAUCGCGGGCGUCCUGGUGCCCGCCAAGGACCAGCCCGGCCGCCAGGAGAAGAUGAGCAUCUACCAGGCCAUGUGGAAGGGCGUGCUGCGGCCCGGCACGGCCCUGGUGCUGCUGGAGGCGCAGGCGGCCACCGGCUUCGUCAUCGACCCCGUGCGCAACCUGAGGCUGUCGGUGGAGGAGGCCGUGGCCGCGGGCGUGGUGGGCGGCGAGAUCCAGGAGAAGCUGCUGUCGGCCGAGCGCGCCGUCACCGGCUACACCGACCCCUACACCGGGCAGCAGAUCUCCCUCUUCCAGGCCAUGCAGAAGGACCUCAUCGUCCGGGAGCACGGCAUCCGCCUGCUGGAGGCCCAGAUCGCCACGGGCGGCGUCAUCGACCCCGUGCACAGCCACCGCGUGCCCGUGGACGUGGCCUACCGGCGCGGCUACUUCGACGAGGAGAUGAACCGUGUCCUGGCCGACCCCAGCGACGACACCAAGGGCUUCUUCGACCCCAACACGCACGAGAACCUCACGUACGUGCAGCUGCUGCGCCGCUGCGUGCCCGACCCGGACACCGGGCUCUACAUGCUGCAGCUGGCAGGCCGGGGCUCCGCCGUGCACCAGCUGAGCGAGGAGCUGCGCUGUGCCCUGCGCGACGCCCGCGUGACGCCAGGCUCGGGCGCCCUCCAGGGCCAGAGCGUCUCCGUCUGGGAGCUCCUCUUCUACCGCGAGGUGUCCGAGGACCGGCGCCAGGACCUGCUGAGCAGAUACCGGGCGGGCACGCUGACCGUGGAGGAGCUGGGCGCCACCCUCACCUCGCUGCUGGCCCAGGCCCAGGCCCAGGCCCGGGCCGAGGCCGAGGCCGGGAGCCCGCGCCCAGACCCCCGGGAGGCCCUGCGUGCGGCCACCAUGGAGGUCAAGGUGGGCCGCCUCCGGGGGCGCGCGGUGCCCGUGUGGGACGUGCUGGCGUCCGGCUACGUGAGCAGGGCCGCCCGGGAGGAGCUGCUGGCCGAGUUUGGCUCGGGGACCCUGGACUUGCCCGCGCUGACCCGCCGGCUGACCGCCAUCAUCGAGGAGGCCGAGGAGGCCCCCGGGGCCCGGCCGCAGCUCCAGGACGCCUGGCGCGGCCCGCGGGAGCCAGGGCCAGCCGGGCGAGGGGACGGCGACUCGGGGCGCUCCCAGCGAGAGGGCCAGGGGGAGGGCGAGACCCAGGAGGCCGCCGCCGCCACCGCCGCCGCCCGCCGCCAGGAGCAGACCCUGCGUGAUGCCACCAUGGAGGUGCAGCGCGGGCAGUUCCAGGGGCGGCCGGUCUCCGUGUGGGACGUCCUCUUCUCCUCGUACCUGAGCGAGGCCCGCCGAGACGAGCUCCUGGCCCAGCACGCGGCCGGCGCCCUGGGCCUGCCCGACCUCGUCGCCGUCCUCACCCGGGUCAUCGAGGAGACGGAGGAGCGGCUCAGCAAGGUGUCCUUCCGCGGCCUGAGGCGCCAGGUGUCCGCCUCCGAGCUGCACACGUCCGGGAUCCUGGGCCCCGAGACCCUGCGGGACCUGGCCCAGGGCACUAAGACGCUGCAGGAGGUGACGGAGAUGGACUCGGUCAAGCGCUACCUGGAGGGCACCAGCUGCAUCGCGGGCGUCCUGGUGCCCGCCAAGGACCAGCCCGGCCGCCAGGAGAAGAUGAGCAUCUACCAGGCCAUGUGGAAGGGCGUGCUGCGGCCCGGCACGGCCCUGGUGCUGCUGGAGGCGCAGGCGGCCACCGGCUUCGUCAUCGACCCCGUGCGCAACCUGAGGCUGUCGGUGGAGGAGGCCGUGGCCGCGGGCGUGGUGGGCGGCGAGAUCCAGGAGAAGCUGCUGUCGGCCGAGCGCGCCGUCACCGGCUACACCGACCCCUACACCGGGCAGCAGAUCUCCCUCUUCCAGGCCAUGCAGAAGGACCUCAUCGUCCGGGAGCACGGCAUCCGCCUGCUGGAGGCCCAGAUCGCCACGGGCGGCGUCAUCGACCCCGUGCACAGCCACCGCGUGCCCGUGGACGUGGCCUACCGGCGCGGCUACUUCGACGAGGAGAUGAACCGUGUCCUGGCCGACCCCAGCGACGACACCAAGGGCUUCUUCGACCCCAACACGCACGAGAACCUCACGUACGUGCAGCUGCUGCGCCGCUGCGUGCCCGACCCGGACACCGGGCUCUACAUGCUGCAGCUGGCAGGCCGGGGCUCCGCCGUGCACCAGCUGAGCGAGGAGCUGCGCUGUGCCCUGCGCGACGCCCGCGUGACGCCAGGCUCGGGCGCCCUCCAGGGCCAGAGCGUCUCCGUCUGGGAGCUCCUCUUCUACCGCGAGGUGUCCGAGGACCGGCGCCAGGACCUGCUGAGCAGAUACCGGGCGGGCACGCUGACCGUGGAGGAGCUGGGCGCCACCCUCACCUCGCUGCUGGCCCAGGCCCAGGCCCAGGCCCGGGCCGAGGCCGAGGCCGGGAGCCCGCGCCCAGACCCCCGGGAGGCCCUGCGUGCGGCCACCAUGGAGGUCAAGGUGGGCCGCCUCCGGGGGCGCGCGGUGCCCGUGUGGGACGUGCUGGCGUCCGGCUACGUGAGCAGGGCCGCCCGGGAGGAGCUGCUGGCCGAGUUUGGCUCGGGGACCCUGGACUUGCCCGCGCUGACCCGCCGGCUGACCGCCAUCAUCGAGGAGGCCGAGGAGGCCCCCGGGGCCCGGCCGCAGCUCCAGGACGCCUGGCGCGGCCCGCGGGAGCCAGGGCCAGCCGGGCGAGGGGACGGCGACUCGGGGCGCUCCCAGCGAGAGGGCCAGGGGGAGGGCGAGACCCAGGAGGCCGCCGCCGCCACCGCCGCCGCCCGCCGCCAGGAGCAGACCCUGCGUGAUGCCACCAUGGAGGUGCAGCGCGGGCAGUUCCAGGGGCGGCCGGUCUCCGUGUGGGACGUCCUCUUCUCCUCGUACCUGAGCGAGGCCCGCCGAGACGAGCUCCUGGCCCAGCACGCGGCCGGCGCCCUGGGCCUGCCCGACCUCGUCGCCGUCCUCACCCGGGUCAUCGAGGAGACGGAGGAGCGGCUCAGCAAGGUGUCCUUCCGCGGCCUGAGGCGCCAGGUGUCCGCCUCCGAGCUGCACACGUCCGGGAUCCUGGGCCCCGAGACCCUGCGGGACCUGGCCCAGGGCACUAAGACGCUGCAGGAGGUGACGGAGAUGGACUCGGUCAAGCGCUACCUGGAGGGCACCAGCUGCAUCGCGGGCGUCCUGGUGCCCGCCAAGGACCAGCCCGGCCACCAGGAGAAGAUGAGCAUCUACCAGGCCAUGUGGAAGGGCGUGCUGCGGCCCGGCACGGCCCUGGUGCUGCUGGAGGCGCAGGCGGCCACCGGCUUCGUCAUCGACCCCGUGCGCAACCUGAGGCUGUCGGUGGAGGAGGCCGUGGCCGCGGGCGUGGUGGGCGGCGAGAUCCAGGAGAAGCUGCUGUCGGCCGAGCGCGCCGUCACCGGCUACACCGACCCCUACACCGGGCAGCAGAUCUCCCUCUUCCAGGCCAUGCAGAAGGACCUCAUCGUCCGGGAGCACGGCAUCCGCCUGCUGGAGGCCCAGAUCGCCACGGGCGGCGUCAUCGACCCCGUGCACAGCCACCGCGUGCCCGUGGACGUGGCCUACCGGCGCGGCUACUUCGACGAGGAGAUGAACCGUGUCCUGGCCCACCCCAGCGACGACACCAAGGGCUUCUUCGACCCCAACACGCACGAGAACCUCACGUACGUGCAGCUGCUGCGCCGCUGCGUGCCCGACCCGGACACCGGGCUCUACAUGCUGCAGCUGGCAGGCCGGGGCUCCGCCGUGCACCAGCUGAGCGAGGAGCUGCGCUGUGCCCUGCGCGACGCCCGCGUGAUGCCAGGCUCGGGCGCCCUCCAGGGCCAGAGCGUCUCCGUCUGGGAGCUCCUCUUCUACCGCGAGGUGUCCGAGGACCGGCGCCAGGACCUGCUGAGCAGAUACCGGGCGGGCACGCUGACCGUGGAGGAGCUGGGCGCCACCCUCACCUCGCUGCUGGCCCAGGCCCAGGCCCAGGCCCGGGCCGAGGCCGAGGCCGAGGCCGGGAGCCCGCGCCCAGACCCCCGGGAGGCCCUGCGUGCGGCCACCAUGGAGGUCAAGGUGGGCCGCCUCCGGGGGCGCGCGGUGCCCGUGUGGGACGUGCUGGCGUCCGGCUACGUGAGCGGGGCCGCCCGGGAGGAGCUGCUGGCCGAGUUUGGCUCGGGGACCCUGGACUUGCCCGCGCUGACCCGCCGGCUGACCGCCAUCAUCGAGGAGGCCGAGGAGGCCCCCGGGGCCCGGCCGCAGCUCCAGGACGCCUGGCGCGGCCCGCGGGAGCCAGGGCCAGCCGGGCGAGGGGACGGCGACUCGGGGCGCUCCCAGCGAGAGGGCCAGGGGGAGGGCGAGACCCAGGAGGCCGCCGCCGCCGCCCGCCGCCAGGAGCAGACCCUGCGUGAUGCCACCAUGGAGGUGCAGCGCGGGCAGUUCCAGGGGCGGCCGGUCUCCGUGUGGGACGUCCUCUUCUCCUCGUACCUGAGCGAGGCCCACCGAGACGAGCUCCUGGCCCAGCACGCGGCCGGCGCCCUGGGCCUGCCCGACCUCGUCGCCGUCCUCACCCGGGUCAUCGAGGAGACGGAGGAGCGGCUCAGCAAGGUGUCCUUCCGCGGCCUGAGGCGCCAGGUGUCCGCCUCCGAGCUGCACACGUCCGGGAUCCUGGGCCCCGAGACCCUGCGGGACCUGGCCCAGGGCACUAAGACGCUGCAGGAGGUGACGGAGAUGGACUCGGUCAAGCGCUACCUGGAGGGCACCAGCUGCAUCGCGGGCGUCCUGGUGCCCGCCAAGGACCAGCCCGGCCGCCAGGAGAAGAUGAGCAUCUACCAGGCCAUGUGGAAGGGCGUGCUGCGGCCCGGCACGGCCCUGGUGCUGCUGGAGGCGCAGGCGGCCACCGGCUUCGUCAUCGACCCCGUGCGCAACCUGAGGCUGUCGGUGGAGGAGGCCGUGGCCGCGGGCGUGGUGGGCGGCGAGAUCCAGGAGAAGCUGCUGUCGGCCGAGCGCGCCGUCACCGGCUACACCGACCCCUACACCGGGCAGCAGAUCUCCCUCUUCCAGGCCAUGCAGAAGGACCUCAUCGUCCGGGAGCACGGCAUCCGCCUGCUGGAGGCCCAGAUCGCCACGGGCGGCGUCAUCGACCCCGUGCACAGCCACCGCGUGCCCGUGGACGUGGCCUACCGGCGCGGCUACUUCGACGAGGAGAUGAACCGCGUCCUGGCCGACCCCAGCGACGACACCAAGGGCUUCUUCGACCCCAACACGCACGAGAACCUCACGUACCUGCAGCUUCUGCAGAGGGCCACCCUGGACCCUGAGACGGGGCUCCUAUUUCUUUCUCUCUCUCUACAGUGACUGGGCUUCCUCCGUGCAGUUUUCUGCAACUCUGGAGAAGUGGAGGCAUACUUGUGUGUCUGGGUUGUUUUUUUUUUUUUUUUUUUUUUUGUCAUUCUUUAAUUUUGUUGUUUUACCCAUUCGUUAUCUGUGGAAAACGUUUUAAGUUGUCAUGUGACAGAAACUUUUCCUUUGUCCAUCGAGGUGUUUCAUAAGUUUUUUGGUGUGUUUUCUGGGUCGUCUAUGUGUCAUAUGGUUUUACUUUUCUCUCCUUUUUCGUUUUCAGAACAUUUUUCUGUCUGUUUUGGAUUCACUGCUUCCAUUUUACAGAAUGUCACUCUUUAGACUCUCAGUCCAUCAUGCCAUCGGGUACUCUUGUUGCAGUGUAAUUUUUAUUACAUGCGGUUAUUUCCCUAACGAUGUGCUAUUCACGUUCAUCUUCAAACUCAUUUUCCAUCAGCCAGUGUCUACUAUUUAGUGCCCUGGCUCUAUUUCGGUCCUCCUCCCCGGGCUUUCCCUGGCUGCUGUGCUGGCCAAAAGCAUGGGCUUUAUUCUCUCCAUUGGCUGCUGCUCCACCUUAGAGGUGUGACCUCACUAGCGUUGACUGAGCGAGUCUGUUGUGGAGAAGAACUUUUUGUAGUAAUUUACUAGGAAAAAUUCUGAACAAGUAAAAUAUGAAGGAAA